GCGCGGCUGCGGGGCUGGGCGAGCGCAAAGAUGUCCGCGCCCGCUGCCGGGAGGCGAGGUGAGUCUUUGAUCGUAACCAGGAGCCCGGAGCUGAGGCAGUUCCUGCACGUGUCGCGGGGCCGGAGAAGCUAGGGCCAGGUAUUCCAGGGAUGCAAGAAUCCUGCAAAUCUGACGUGUAAACUGCUUCCCCAGCCUCCAGGCGAGCCCAGCUUUUGCCUCAGAUAGGCCCCUUCCUUUUCCUUCUCGGGGAAUCGACCUCGGGAAGGGGUGUGGGCAAAGAGAUGAGGACUCUCCCUCUUCGCCCAGGCCAACUCGGGAUAUCCCGGAGCCUCUGGGGAGGCGGUCACUCCGACGUCUGAGGACCUGGGCCUUGGACCCGGACUCGUUAUGAAGAGCGAUUCUUCGACCUCUGCAGCCCCCCUCAGGGGGCUCGGGGGACCCCUGCGCAGCAGCGAGCCGGUGCGCGCGGUCCCGGCCCGGGCGCCGGCCGUGGACCUUCUGGAGGAGGCGGCCGACCUCCUGGUGGUGCACCUGGACUUCCGGGCGGCGCUGGAGACCUGCGAGCGGGCCUGGCAGAGUCUGGCCAACCACGCCGUGGCAGAGGAACCCGCGGGCACCUCAUUGGAGGUGAAGUGCUCCCUGUGUGUUGUGGGGAUCCAGGCCCUGGCAGAAAUGGAUCGGUGGCAAGAAGUCCUCUCCUGGGUCCUUCAGUAUUACCAGGUCCCUGAAAAGCUACCCCCCAAAGUCCUGGAGCUGUGCAUUCUUUUAUACAGCAAAAUGCAAGAGCCUGGAGCUGUGCUGGAUGUGGUGGGUGCCUGGCUCCAAGACCCAGCCAAUCAAAACCUUCCAGAAUAUGGAGCCUUGGCAGAAUUUCACGUGCAGCGGGUGCUGCUGCCUCUGGGCUGCUUAUCGGAGGCUGAGGAGCUAGUGGUGGGCUCUGCAGCCUUUGGUGAGGAGCGGCGACUGGAUGUACUUCAGGCCAUUCACACAGCGAGGCAGCAGCAGAAACAGGAACACUCAGGCUCUGAGGAGGCCCAGAAGCCAAACCUGGAAGGCUCUGUCUCCCACAAGUUCCUGUCACUACCGAUGUUGGUUCGCCAGCUUUGGGACUCUGCGGUGAGCCACUUCUUUUCUCUGCCCUUCAAAAAGAGUCUCCUGGCUGCCUUGAUCCUCUGUCUCCUGGUGGUGAGAUUUGAUCCAGCUUCCCCUUCCUCCCUGCACUUCCUCUACAAGCUGGCCCAGCUCUUCCGCUGGAUCCGGAAGGCUGCAUUUUCUCGCCUCUACCAGCUCCGCAUCCGUGACUGAGGGUCCCUGCGCACCACAGCCUCUCUGCUCCUCACGUCCGUGGCCACAGAAGCAGAGCGACAGAGCGACACAUCCACAGGCGCCCCUGGGGAAAUGGGACCAGCCUAAUCUCGCGGAGUGCACUGUGUCUUGCUGCCUGGGUGCCCUCUCCUUUGCACCCUACUUCGGCUGGUCGCGGUAGAUGAUGUGGAAACAAAGCAGGACCAGCAGGCACAGCACCUCCAGAACAGUGCCCCGGAUGACCAGAGGCCCCUUGAAAAGGAGGGGUUUGGGGACAGGGACUGUGUCCAUGAAACAUUCCAUCUUCUUGGUGAAGGCAAGGGGUUGGUUCUUCAGGUCAGGAUGUUAAUGGAGCUGGAAGUUCAGAAAAAGCCUGGUGAAGUGACCCUUGGCCUUUCACUUCUUGAGAAACAUACUUCUUUGCUGGGCAUGGUGACUCACGCCUGUAAUCCCAGCACUUUGGAAGGGUGAGGUGGGUGGAUCACUUGUGGCCAGGAGUUCAAAACCUGCCUGGCCAACAUGGUGAAACCCCAUCUCUACUAAAAAUACAAAAAUUAGCUAGAUGUGGUGCACGCCUAUAGUCCUAGCUACUUGGGAGGCUGAGGCAGGAGAAUCACUUGAGCCAGGGAGGCAAAAGUUGCAGUGAGCUGAGAUUGUGCUACCGCACUCUCUCAAAACAAACAAAAAAACAUGCCCCACAGGACAGUACCUUAAUUAGCUAGAGUAGAUCUGAGAGGGCCUCUUCUUGCCUGCACUGUGCUCCCCAGAGCUGAUCUAAUUCUGUAUCAAUAGGCUGUUCCCAUGGUCUUGCCAUGCGCUUGAAGCUGCAGGAGCCUUCUCACUGUUCAGGCUGGGGUGUGGUUUUCAGAACCACCGGGUUGACUACUGAAAACCAAGUGAGCCUUACAGCUCUUAUCGCUGGGUAAAGUGAUCUUGCCUGGUGCCUCUUGGUCUUCAGCUCAAUUUUCCAGGUUGUCCUGGCCAAGUCUUGCUCUGUUACGCUCAGUGCCUCUGCCCACUCUUUCCCCGCCAGCCCUUCCCUCCCGCCCUGCAAACUUGUCCCUUGGCUGUUUCACCAGGUUCUGCCUGUAUCCUUGCCUCCUUGGUACACACCAUUUCAGGUUCUUCCCUUUCUGUGUCCCAUUGUCCUAGUUAUGUUCUGUUGUUUGUGUAAUGCCCAAAUUUUUCUGCUCGUGUGGCCUUGAAAAGUAGGCCAGCCUCAGAGGCUGCUGAGCUGAAAAUGGAACUGAGUAAUCAGGUGAGCUGGAAGGGAUGUGGGGGGCGGGGCAGACGGGAGACAUGGGUUUUGAAGGCAGUGAACAAUAAAACCUUAGGGAGGUGGCACCGAGGCCUUAGCAUUUGAGGAGCUGAAAUGUUUCAGUGUUGUUUUCUCACCAGCCACAAGCAUCUUAUGAGUUUCUGUGCAAGGAAGCGUAGAGCACUGCUGUGCUGUCAGGAUGAAGAAGGGCUUUCUGCAGGGGCUGGCCUUUCUCUACCCAGAGGCCAAGCAGGCUGCCCUGCACUGUGUCCUUGGUGUUGAUGCCCAAAAUAGAGAAGGUGCUUGCUAGCUUUUCCUUGGUACAUUUUCGGGGGUUGCAAGGCAACAAGUUUUCUUUUGUUUUGUUUGUUUGUUUGUUUGUUUGUUUUUGAGAUGGAGUCUCUGUCACCCAGGCUGGAGUGCAGUGGCGUGAUCUCAGCUCACUGCAAGCUCCGCCUCCCGGGUUCAUGCCAUUCUCCUGCCUCAGCCUCCCGAGUAGCUGGGACUACAGGUGCCCACCACCUCGCCUGGCUAAUAUUUUUGUAUUUUUAGUAGAGUCUGGGUUUCACUGUGUUAGCCGGGAUGGUCUCGAUCUCCUGAACUUGUGAUCCACCCACCUAGGCCUCCCAAAGUGCUGGGAUUACAGGUGUGAGCCAUCGCGCCCGGCCAACUUUUCUUUAGAAAAAUGAGUAAAGUAGGUAAACUUCACAGGCCCCUUAGAAUUAAAUCCUUAGGGCAUGGUUCAAGUCUGUAGGAAGCAAAUCUAUACUUUUUUAUAUGGGCUUUUAAGUAAAGCUUAGAACCCUGGGGGGAGAAAAGCAGUCAGGUGAGGUUUGAGAUUCCUUCUAUAGAAUGAUUUCUUAAAAUGAAAAUCUGGGCCCACUUAACUACCCUAGAUAAAACGCUUCAAUGGCUUCCCAUGGCUCACUGGAUAACAUCUAAAUUCUUCAUGGAAUUGAAGGCCCCUAUGUGCUGGUUUUGGCUAAGAUCUCCCCUUUGAUGUGGGUCCCCUGUUGAUUAUAUGUGCGGCCUUCCAGCUGCCCACCAUCACAGCUACAGCUCGCUCCCCUUGGCCUCUGUGCCUUGGCUCGCACUGUUCCUACUGAAGGCCUAGCACCUGCUCUUGGCCUGGUGAGCCCCUCCACCUUCCAGGCUUACUCAAAGAAUUCUUUCUGCCCCUCCCUGUGUCCCGGGACCUGUUUCAUAUCGCUUCUGUGGUCGUGACCCCAUGGUCUUGUAAUUGUGAACUUCUUUGCUGCCCCUUCGAAGCUGGGGAGUGCUUGUUGCAGAUGCAUCCAAGAGGGGUAAUUGCGUAUCAACAGUGGAUUUGCUGGUUGUUUCUACAGGGUUCUGAAGCAUGCAACAUAGAACAGAUACCUUUAAAUUUAGGGGCGCUAAGGAAAGCAGGAACCAGUAAUCCUCUUCUGUGGUGGGAUGGGAGGGUGGGGGAGAGGGGUGGAAUGGAGAGGAAACAGGCUAUUGUUGGCCAGCCCUGGGUGGAGGUGGGUGCAAGCAGGACAGAUAGUGCCUGGGGGUGGGGGCGGAGGGUUCGCCUCUAGGAAGGGGCUAGAAGGGAUGAGGAAAUAGUUCAUAGCUUCGUGCAGGUGAUCCCUAUUCUGCGUGUAUGUGUUUGCACAUGAGUGUUUGUAGACCAUAGACCAUUAAAAAAUACGGAAUUCAAAAGUUACAAAAAGGGUAUUCUUGGAAAAGAAAGUUGUUUUUUUUUAGUCUUGCUGUGUUGCCCAGGCUGGACCUGAACUCCUGGGCUUGAGCAAGUCUUCCCCUCAGCCUCUGGAGUAGCUGGGCCUACAGUGUGUGCUGCCACACCCAGCUAAUACAGUCUUUCUACUCCCGCUCUCUAUUCCCCAGUUUCUUGCCCAGAGGCAACCCUUGCCAGUCUGUUUAUCCCUCCAGAUACAGUCUCUGAUAGUAAACUUUUCUUUCUCUUACACAAAUGAUAGUAGUCACAUACACUACACACACUGUGCCACGUUUAAAAAGAAAAAAAACAAUUCUCGGCUGGGCGCGGUGGCGCAUGCCUGUAAUCCCAGCACUUUGGGAGGCCAAGGUGGGUGAAUCACCUGAAGUCAGGAGUUCGAGAUCAGCAUGGCCAACAUGGUGAAACCCCAUCUCUACUAAAAAUACAAAAAAAAAAUGAGCCGGGCAUGGUGGUGGGUACCUGUAAUCCCAGCUACUCAGGAGGCUGAGGCAGGAGAAUCACUUGAACCCGGGAGGCAAGGGUUGCAGUGAGCUGAGAUCGCGCCAUUGCACUCCCACCUGGGCAACAAAGAGUGAAACUUGGUCUCAGAAACGAAACAAAACACAAAAACCUUUCUCAGUCCCAGCAUAUGUGGAGCAGCCUCAUUCUUCAUAGCUGUGUGUCAUUCCGUUGCGUGAUGGGGUCACAGAGCACAGACCUGGUGCCCUUUUCCUUUUUAAUAUGUGGAAACCCCUCCAUGCUUUCCAAAGCCUACAAGUACAGCAGCCCCAAGUUUAGGGUGAGCAGCAGUGGUCAGAGCUCUUUACUAUUACUUUUGGGCAAACGCAAGCCAGGCUGGCAACCACCACUGCCGCCGAGGGGAGAUACAAGCAGGCCAGUUCACACUCUGGACGUUCAGUUUCUUUCUACAUCUAGAAGGUGGCCUCUGCUAUCCACUUAAAGCAGCCCAAGGAACUGUCAGAAAGCGAAAGUGAUGACAUGAACCGCGAGUAGGGCACCUCCCUGUGCCGUCGUCUGCUUUCCUUCCUCCCUCCCAGCCUCCCUGUGCCGUCCUCUGCUUUCCUCCCUCCCAGCACGGAAAAGCCGUGGGGCCGAUGGACUUUGGCCUCACAUCCACAGAUGGGGCCUGUGGGAAUUCUACUGAUUUACUCUCUGGCCUAGUCAAGCAACCCACCCACGGCCUGGCCAAGGUCGGCCUCACCGCCCUGGCCUAGCACCUUUGGAAACUGAAUACAUGGAGUGUUAACCAGAAAAAUGUCUGGCCCUUUUGCCUCGCUGCCUCUGGAAACCUCAGUGUUUCGGGCUGGUAGGAAGCUACAGGACAGACAGUGGGCACGGUGCCUAGCAGCCUGUCGCGCCCCCGCCCGCCUCUGCAUUCCUCCAGCGGUGGUGUACGGAUCCAGACAUUGUUUGCCACCUCUAGGCCUCUUGAUAAAACAGCAAGUAUUUUUCUUGUCUUAAAGCAAUGCAUGUAUAUUUUAGAAAAUAUUAAUUGCAUAGAAGGAAAUACAGGACUCGUGAUCCCACCACUCAGAAAUAAUUACUAUUAAUACGGUUGAUUUUCUUUCAGCUUUUUUCCCCCUAAUUAAUUAACUAAUUCUUUUUUUUCCUGCAACUCCUGCUUCACAGACUUUUUUUUUUUUUUUAACUUGGCAUGGUGGCUCACACCUAUAAUCCCAGCACUUUGGGAGGCCAGAGUGGGAGGAUUGCUUGAGCCUAGGAGUUCAAAGCUAGCCUGGGCAACCUAGUGGGACCCCAUUUCUUUUUUUUGGGGGGGGGGUGGGUUAUAAAAGCCCUUUUAUAAAGCCAAUUUUAAACAAGAAAAAAACAAAAAGUUUACAAAAGAAAAAAAGAUACAGAAAAAGAAUAACUUGCUUCAUAUGUCCCAAAAAGAGAAAAAAAUAAACGGGACAAUGCCAACAUGCUCAACAAUAAAGGGUUCUUUUUCUUACUUUUUUAAUACAAAAUACAAGCAAAGGAUACACAUACUUAAAACAGAGCUCAGGAGCAGACACGCAGUCCUGGGAACCCUUCAAUAAGAGCAAAGCAGGAGUUUGUUUUUUCUUUGUGCAGAUACAUACAGAGACUGGGAUAUGUAAAAAUUAAGUAUCACAAAAGACCAUCACACGAUUCUACCAAUGCAUGUUGCAUCUAUAAUUCACGAACAUGGUCAACAAGAUCAUGUUCACUUCAACCCCAUUUCAUUUAAAUUAAAGAAAAAAACCUGGCCGGGCGCGGUGGCUCACGCCUGUAAUCCCAGCACCUUGGGAAGCCGAGGCAGGUGGAUCACGAGGUCAGGAGAUCGAGACCAUCCUGGCUAACACGGUGAAAUCCCAUCUCUACUAAAAAAAUACAAAAAAUUAGCCGGGCGUGGUGGCGGGUGCCUGUAGCCCCAGCUACUCGGGAGGCUGAGGCAGAAGAAUGGCGUGAACCCAGGAGGCGGAGCUUGCAGUGAGCCUAGAUGGCGCCACUGCACUCCAGCCUGGGGGACAGAGCAAGACUCCGUCUUAAAAAAAAAAAAAACAAAAAUAAACCUUUUAAAUAAAGUGGUUACAUUCUAACUUUAACUUCCUUAGUACCAUGCUGCAGGUUUCAGCACUGUUAAGGUAUUGCAAGAAUGCCCAACCCUCUGGUGUCUGAUUGUGUAUCUAGCAACAUUGCAGUAUGAAGAAAAGAGAUGCCCCGGGUACGACCCCAUUUCUAUUAAAAAUAAAUGUAAACACCCAACCCUCUUGGCAGCCCAUGCACUUGAGAACCUGUAGAAAAUGGCAGUGUGCAACCAGCAUGGCUGCGAGCUCAGCGUCUUCACUAGAGAGAGUGGAGGUGGUUAGGAAAGGGCAGGCGGGAAGGGGCCAUGUUGGCCGGACAACUGCAGGUGAAGAUGGGAUUGUGAAGUACAGUCCAAGGCCCACUCACCAAGGGCUGGAUCCAAAUAUGUGGGGUUGGGAUUCUGUGACCUACUUCCAAUUUUAAUAUUGACCUGAGCUCAUAUUUAGCUCUACAUGUUUCCCAGCUCGUAUUUUCCAACAGCCCCUUUAAAACUUUUAGCAUCCUCUUGUCACUUUUGUACUAUCCAAGGUGGGACGGACAGGUGUCAGAUAAUAGCAGAGACUUGGUGAAGAAAUGAAAGCACUUUUGUAGAAGAGUGUCAUUUCAGAAAAAAGCCUUUUUUUUUUGAGAUGGAGUCUCGCUCUGUCACCCAGGCUGGAAUGCAGUGGCGUGAUCUCAGCUCACUGCAAGCUCCGCCUCCUGGGUUCACACCAUUCUCCUGCCUCAGCCUCCCGAGUGGCUGGGACUAUAGGCGCCCGCCACCACGCCUGGCUAAUUUUUUGGUAUUUUUAGUAGAGACUGGGUUUCACCGUGUUAGCCAGGAUGGUCUCGAUCUCCUGACCUCGUGAUCCGCCUCCCACAGUGCUGGGAUUACAGGCGUGAGCCACGGCACCUGGAGAGAAAAAAGCUUCUUUAAUGACGACCUCAACAUAAUUUACAUGGAGAAGUUUCUUAGGUGGAAAACCGAUUUGUAUGGUCCUCAGAAUGUAACCUACAGGUUCUUGCCCUCAGAAAAAUGCAUGCAUACUUUUAUGUUACAGGCUUAUUUUCCAAAUGCGGUAGAGGGCCAUCCCUUCUUUGGCUUCUUGCCUUGUCUCUGACCCCACUGACUGCCCCUUUUCUGCCUCCAUAGCUAGUUUCUUAUUUUCCUUUGGCUUUUUUUUUCUUUUCUUUUCUUUUCUUCUUUUUUUUUUUGAGAUGGAAUCUUGCUCUUGUCACCUAGGCUGGAGUGCAGUGGUGCGAUCUCGGCUCACUGCACCCUCCUCUUGGGUUCAAGCCAGCGAGGUAGAUAUUAUCAUUUUAGAGACAGCAAAACAGACUCAGAGGGGCUAAUGUGCCCAGUGCCCCACCGCUUUUAAAUGGUAGAGCUGGGAUUUGAAUCUAGGCAUACAGGUACCAGGAUUUCUGUUCUUAUCUCCCCCAUAGCACCUGGAAUGAGGCCAUCCAUGUAAGAGGCCAAGUAAUAAAGAUUUGUUGAAUGAACUUGGAUUUUGGCCUUAGGAAUUAGGGAAGGAAGAAAUAGAAGCAGCAAGAGUUGGUGAGCAAUAAGACCCGCACCAGGGCUGAAGGGUGGAGGUGGGGCAGGGGAGGGCUCUGUGCUUUGGCAUCUGUUUAGUAGUAUCGUCGCCCAGCUCCCUCCAGAGAAAGAGCAGGAGGUGUUCUUCUCAGAUGUACCAGCAAUGACAAAGCCUGGCGGGUGUCCUCCUGGGUAGGUAUAAAUACAAGCUGGUAGUUUCAUUGGAUGACUCACACAGAUAAGCCAUGCUCUUGGUUACCAGUGGACUUAGCUGGGUCUCAAAGAAUGGGCUGCUUUCUCUGGAAAGCUGGGGAGCUGGUAAAAUUUUUUGGUCGCCCCACCAGAGACAUCCUACCCAUUCCCAGUCCCUCUGUGGGCUCUGACAUCUCUGUCCGGCGGGCACCCCCUGCUCUGGAACAUUCUGGGAAUGCUUCCCACUCCCCUUUUAGUACUUGUUUGUGUUCUGUCCUGUUCCUGGAUUUCAUGGUCUCCAUGGUGACAAGUGCUUGUUUUCAGAGGUGCUAAAGACAAUGGCUAAAAGAUGUGCUCUAUUAAUCCUCCCAGGAAACAUAUUUUGCAAAAGCCUUUUUUUUUUUUUUUUUGAGAAACAAGGCCUAACCCCAAUGGAGUAAUUUGCUGCGUAAAUGAGAGACAUCAUGGGAUUGUGGUUAAGAGUGUGGGUCCCAGACCCAUAAUGCCCAAGUUUGUAUCUUUUUUUUUUGAGACAGAGUCUCACUCUGUCGUCCAAGCUGGAGGGCAGUGGCAUGAUCUCGACACACUGCAACAUCCACUUCCUAGGUUCAAGCGAUUCUCUUGCCUCAGCCUUCCGAGUAGCUGGAACUACAGGCACACACUACCACGCCUGGCUAAUUUUUGAAUUUUUAGUAGAGACGGGGUUUUACCAUGUUGGCCAGGCUGGUCUUGAACUCUUGACCUCAAGUGAUCUGCAUGCCUCACCUCCCAAAGUGUUGGGAAUACAGGCAUGAGCCACCACACCCGGCCUGAGUUUGUAUCUUGACUCACCUGCUUUGACCUUCAAAUAAUCUUUCCUGUGCCUCAGUUACUUCAUAGGUUUGUUGUGAGGAUUAACUGGUGCUAAUCCAUGUAAAACACUGAAAAGGUGCAUAGCAUGUAGUGAGCAGGUGCUAGUUAUUAUUACUGUUGCUCUUAAUUAAGUGAGGUAAGGAGGGGAGAGUUGGAGUGGUAGAACCCAGCAUCUUGUGAACAUCAGACCACAGAAAAGGCAGCACUUCUGAUUCCUGUUCUUAGCCUAGGAACUAGGCUUUGCAAAUGGCUCUGAAUUUUUUUUUUUUUUUUGAGAUGGAGUCUCGCUCUGUCGCCCAGGCUGGAGUGCAGUGGCACGAUCUCAGCUCACUGCAAGCUCUGCCUCCCAGGUUCAUGCCAUUCUUCUGCCUCAGCCUCCCGAAUAGCUGGGACUACAGGCGCCCGCCACCACACCCGGCUAAUUUUUUGUAUUUUUAGUAGAGAUGGGGUUUCACCGUGUUAGCCAGGAUGGUCUCGAUCUCCUGACCUUGUGAUCUGCCCACCUCGGCCUCCCAAAGUGCUGGGAUUACAGGCGUGAGCCACCACGCCCGGCCGGCUCUGAUUUCUUAAAGUGCUAAGCCUUUUUAUAUAUUCAUUUCAGACCAUGUUUAAUUUUCUAAAUAUGCAAUACAUUCAUAGGGUUUUUGAAAAGGCUUGAAAAAGUCUAGUGUGAAAGCAGUCUGUAUUAGUCCAUUUUCACACUGCUUUAGAGAAGUAUCAGAGACUGGGUAAUUGUUGAAGAAAAGAGGUUUAACUGACUCACAGUUCUGCAUGGCUGUGAGGCCUCAGGAAACAAGCAGUCAUAGUGGAAGGCAAAGGGGAAGCAAGGCACAUCUUACAUGGCAGCAGCAGAGAGAAUGAGGGGGGAUGCCACACUUUAAAACCAUCAGAACUCGUGAGAACUGACUCACUAUCACAAGAACAACAGGGGAGAAACUGUUCCUGUGAUCCAGUCACCUCCCACCAGGUCCCUCCUCCGACGUGGGGAUUACAGUUUGAGAUGAGAUUUGAGUGGGGACACAGAGCCAAACCAUAUCACCUCCCAUCUCUUCAUUUAGCAAGUUCACCUACCCCAAUGGCAGCUAUGGCCGUUAGUUUUUUUUUUUUUUCUUUUUUUUGAGACAGAGCCUCACUCUGUCGCCCAGGCUGGAGUGCAGGGGUGUGAUCUCGGCUCACUGCAAGCUCCGCCUUCCGGGUUCACGCCAUUCUCCUGCCUCAGCCUCCCAAGUGGCUGGGACUACAGGCUCCUGCCACCGCGCCCGGCUAAUUUUUUGUAUUUUUAGUAGAGACGGGGUCUCACCGUGUUAGCCAGGAUGGUCUUGAUCUCCUGACCUCGUGAUCCACUUGCCUCGGUCUCCCAAAGUGCUGGGAUUACAGGCAUGAGCCACCGUGCCUGGCCACAGCCAUUAGUUUUAAAUUUACUCUUCCAGAGGUAAAUUUAAUACACCAAUACAAAACCAGUAUGGAUAUAGAUCCUAGUUUCUUCUCCUUUUUAUAAAAAAAACCUGUAGUAUAUUAUGUACUCUGUUUUAUUCCUUCCUUUUUUUUUCUUAUAAAAAAUACAGAGAUGGGGUCUUACUACACUGACCAGGCUGGUGUUGAACUUGCCUCAAGUGAUCCUCCCAUCUUGACCUCCCAAAGUGCUGGGAUUAUAGGCAUAAGCCACCACACCCAGAUGAUUUUUUUAUUUUUCAAAGAAGUGGCAUGAUUUUGAUGACAAUAAAGGACAAUAUGUAAUUAAUGGUAAUUAUAAUACAGCCUUCUAGAGGCCAGGUGCAGUGGCCCAUGCCCGUAAUCCCACCACUUUGGGUGGCCAAGGCAGGUGGAUCAUGAGGCCAGGAGUUUGAGACCAGCCUGGCCAACAUGAUGAAACCCCAUCUCUUCAAAAAAUCUAAAAAUUAGCUGGGUGUGGUGGCGUGCACCUGUAAUCUCAGCUACUUGGGAGGCUGAGGCACAAGAAUCACUUGAACCCAGGAGGCGGAGGUUGCAGUGGGCCGAGAUCGAGCCACUGCACUCCAGCCUGGGCAACAGAGCGAGACUCUGUCUCACACAUACACACACAAAAAAAGUAUAAAUAUAUAGCUUUCUAGAUAUAGGAUUGGACUGGUUUUGGUUCUGGCUCUGUUACUAAUUUGCCCUAUAACUUUGCAUAAGUCAUUUAAUCUCGGGUCCAAUUUUUCUCACCUCCAAGAUGGGGACAAAAAUUAUCUUCCUUGGCUGGGUGCGGUGGCUCAUGCCUGCAAUCCCAGCACUUCGGGAGGCCAAGACCAGCCUGGCCAACAUGAUGAAACCCCACCUCUACUAAAAAUACAAAAAUUAGCUGGGUGUGAUGGUGCACACCUUUAAUCCCAGCUACUCAGGAGGAGGCUGAGGCAGGAGAAUCUCUGGAACCUGGGAGGCAGAGGUUGCAGUGAGCUGAGAUCCUGCCACUGCACUCCAGUCUGGGCGACAGAGUGAGAUUCUGUCUCAAAAAAAAGAAAAAAGAAAAAAAAAUUACCUCCCUCAUUUUCUUUAUAAUAUUAUUGUGUAAAAUGAGUAAAAGUCUAUAAGAAAAACUUUGAAAAGUAUUAAGUAAUACACAUGUGUAUGUGUGCGUGUGUAGACAUAUAUAUAUAAUAUAUAUACACAUAUGCAAUGGAGUAAUGAAAAUACUAUAUAAUAAAUAUAAAAUGGAUUAAAACUAUAUAAAAUAGAUGCAUGAAAUGGCUACAUAGAUAUGGAUGUUUGCAUAUAGGCACAUUUAGCUGGAUUAAGUUAGAUUUAAAUGGUCCAAUAGAGAACUGUGCAUACAAUUACAUAGGCAACCACAAAUCAACCCUUUCUCUGGGCUAUCUAAAAUAAUCAGGUACUAGACCAAAAAAUGACAUGCUGUCUGCCUUACCUUUUAGUGAUGAUUUGUAGGAAGAGGAAGGUAGGGGCUGGUGAGUGGAAAAGUAGUAGAGUUUGUGAGGGAAUGUUCUGUAUGUCUGAAGACAAAGUCUGGAGAUUGGUGGGCCAGAAGGUGUGAAUCUACUCUGAAGGACAGGCAAGAGUCCAGCCCAGGGAAAAAGGUGCAGAUGGGUAGGAUUUGGGUGGGUACUUGAAUUAAAAAAAUGAAUUUGUGAGGCAAUAUUGCUGGAGUCAAAACCAAAAAAUCAAAUUGACCAGGGCAAAAAAUAGCCUGGGGCCUAGCAUGGCUCUGCUGCCACGUAGGAUGACUGGACCUCUUUCCAGGUUCGUGUUAACAGUCCAUACUACUUAUGGUAUACGUGAAAUGCUUUCUAUUCAUUCAAGCAACCUUACUAAAAACACCCCAUGAAAAUAAAAGUCUAUAUCUUCCCUUCAAUAUACAUUCAUAUGUGCUUAUUUUAAGCAUAUAUCUACCAAUUUGAGUUUGGCAUUCUUUUUCAUUUAAUAUUAUUACCUAUUCAGCUUCCAACAUUAUCACUUCCUUACUACACACAUUUGUUUCCUAGGACUGCUGUUAACAAAUUGCCACAAAUGUAUGGCUUAAAACAACAGAAAUUUAUUAUCUCACAGCUCUGAAGGCCAGAAGUCAGCCAAAGCCUCUGCCUCUGAAGGCUGUAGGCAAGAUUCCUUCCUUGUUUCUUCCAGCUUCUGCUGGCUCUAAGUGUUCCCUGGCCUGCGACAGCAUCACUCCAAUCCCUGCCUCAGUCUUCGCUUGACCUUCUUCGUACCUCUGUAUCUUCUCUGCCAAGGAUGCAUGUCACUGAAUUUAAGAGCCACCCUAAUCCAGGAUGAUCUCAUCUUGAGGUCCUCAAUUACAUCAAGAUCCUUAUUCCAAAUAAUGUCACAUUCUGAGAUUUUAGGCAAACAUAUCUUUGGGGGGCCAAAAUUCAAUCCCCUAAUCCAUGUUAGUAACCAUGCAGUGUUCCUUCUUAUUUCUAUGUUGACCUUUUCAGCUCUUUCUAUUUAUUGUUAUUAUUUUUGAGAUAGAGUUUCAAUCUUGUUGCCCAGGCUGGAGUGCAAUGGUGCAAUCUUGGCUCACGGCAACCUCCGCCUCCCAGGUUCAAGCAAUUCUCCUGCCUCAGCCUCCUGAGUAGCUGGUAUGACAGGCAUGCACCACCAUGCCCAGCUAAUUUUAUAUUUUUAGUAGAGGCAGGGUUUCGCUGUGUUGGCCAGACUGGUCUCAAACUCCUGAUCUUGGGUGAUCUGCCCUCCUCAGCCUCCCAAAGUGCUGGGAUUAGAGGCGUGAGCCACCAUGCCUGGCCAGCUCUUUCUAACUAAAAAAUAAUAAUAAUAAUAAUAAAAAAUAAAAGAUGAUACUUGCAAAAUACCUCAAGUGUACCUCAUUUACCUCAAAUAUACCUCAUGGUCCGAAAGUAUUUAGUCAGCAAUGUACCAUUAUAGAAAAACACAUAGCUUGUGGCUCCAACUUUAAAACCAGAAUAACCAAGUGAAAAGUCAGUACAGAUUCUCACUUCUACUUAAAAAAUCAAAGGUACACAUUGGGAAUUGAACAGCUAUGUUUUUUCUUCUUUCUAGAGAUGUGACAUACAUAUUUUCUGGUCAGUAAUAUUCUACCAAUGGUAUUAAUUCAAAGCAGGUAGAUGACCAGCGAUGCUGUUUACUACAUCCUACGCAUGCUGAGAUAGAUGAGUGGGACACCAUCUCGGUAGGAAAGAGUUUGACAGGAAGAAGAAAUUGCAGAGUCCCUGCCUGUCCCAGAGAACCUAACAAACUGAUCUAUAUGGAAAGGAUUUUCAGCAAACAUGCACAAACACAGUUAAUAUGCUGGAAGAAGAGGAUAGCUUUUAGUCUAUUUCCAGCACACGGCCUACACUCACUGGUACCCCAUACAACAGGAAUGAAUGCCGACUUAGCAUUUUUGCCUUCACAGCGCUGGCAACUAAAAGGCUCACAGAUACUCUGAUCUUUAAGCAGAUAAUCAUGGAAUUCUCAACAUCAUAUCCACUAGGUUAGGCUGAGGGUUCAUCUAUAAAAGUAUUUUUCCAAAAAUAAUGCUUAAAAGAGACUUCUAGAAACAGUGGGACUGUAUCAGGAUCAACAGAAGACUUCUUGACCCAAAGAUUCAAAUAUAGAACUAGGAAUUGAUUUUCACAUGUAGUUUUUAGGUAAAGGACAUCUCUUUCAGUUGAUUCCUACAGCCAAGACUAGCUUUGAUCCUGGGAGAUUCAGAAACCUCAAGAUGGGUAGCUGGCUUGAGUAACAUCCUAGAUAAUAGUCCCAGUCAAAAACCCCAUUGAGGUUGAAGGACUGGAAACUGACCUGUGUGAAAAAGAGCUAUCAGUGCAGGAAAAGACUCAUGCUGAUUUUGACCUUCCUCUGACCCUUUUCCCUCAACUGCUUGGUGGGGAGUAGCGAGGAGAAGGAGCAUGUGGCACCCUCAUUGGAGGCUGGAGCACUGCUGCAGAAAGUGAUCUCUUACUCAUACUUCAAGACACAGCCUAAGUAUGACCACCUGUAUGGACCCUUCCCUAAUGCCCAGGAUCAAGAAAAGAAUGUGGCCACCUUCCAAGGCUCAGAGUAGCUGUGCAAUGACUUGUGUCAAAACCCGAUCCAGAGCAGCAGUGAUGAAAUCACCCUCUCCUUUAAGACCUGGCAUUACAAUGGCCUCAUCCUGCAUGUGGGCAAGUCAGCUCUCUGAUGGAUGGUGCAAUUUCCUUGGUCAUUAACCUGAGGUCUGGGGCCUUUAAAGCUAUUGAGGAGCCAGUGAAUGGAGAAUUCGACAACGCCUGGCAUGAUUGAGGGUGACACAUCACGGCAGAUGAUGGCUGAGGAGACAUUGCCCAGAAGUCUCAUCUUAGGUGGUUGAGUAGGAAGUUUGUGAAGCAGGUGGUGGGUGAGAUGGAGUGGGUAGAGAUUCAGGUAUGGAGAUGUCAGUGUCUAACUUUCUUCUAGUCUUUGCAAUUUCACAAGGAAAAUCACUAAAAUGUGCGUCUCUUCAUUUAAAAGAAAAAAAAGUUCAUGCCAAAGCUGCUGGGACAAAGAGGACUCAUGAUAGUGGGUUAUUCCACACUGUUGACACACUGAAUGUAUGCUGGCAGAAGGGCCUCAGGUGGAAUGCUGGGCAUGGGUUUGCCCCACAGCAGUCUGAUUCAAAAGCACCUGAGAGAUGGGAGGAGUACUAGGGUUACUAAACACAAGAAGGUGUUUCAGGAGAAACACAUCAAGCCAUUUGUUUUUGACCCUUAAUACUUAACAUGAAUGAUGAGUUGCAGAACAGUCAGUCUUUCCAAGAUGUAUUGUUCUAUCCUCAAUAGCUGCAGCCUCUCCAAGCCAGUGGGCUGGUGACAUCCAGGAUGAUCCUCUUCCUUGCCUGGAGGUGGGAUCUAGUGCCACAGCUUGUUCGGGGAAGCUGGCAUAGAAGAUGAUUUGCUCAACAAAGUCACCGCUAAACUAUCGCUUAGGUCUAGUCCCCGGCCUAUGGCACCAAGUACUCCUGGUAGUACUUGUACACAGAAUUUCUCUAUAAUAACCAGAACAUGUCAUCCAUGGUAAUGUCUGCUACAUAUCCAACCACAGCAUCAAAUUCUGUCUGAUGAAGGGCACCAGCCCCUUCAUCUUUAUCAUGCCUAAUAUUGUGAAGGCCAUGUGCUAAAUCCAGCAAUCCGCUCCAGUAGGUGUCCUUCAGGAUACUUUUCUGUCAAGUAAAUACAUUUAUUAAAAAUAGGCAUGUAGCCGGGCGCAGUGGCUCACACCUGUAAUCGCAGUACUUUAGGAGGCUGAGGCGGGCGAAUCACGAGGUCAGGAGUUCGAGACCAGCCUGGCCAACACGGUGAAACCCCAUCUCUACUAAAAAUACAAAAAAUUAGCUGGGCAUGGUGGCGUGUGCCUGUAAUCCCAGAUACUCAGGAGGCUGAGGCAGGAGAAUUGCUUGAACCCAGGAGGCAGAGGUGGCAGUGAGCCGAGAUCGUGCGAUCGUGCUAUUGCACUCCAGCCUGGGCGACAGUGUGCGACUGCAUCUCAAAAAAAAAAAAAAAAAAAAGGCAUGUAAAAGUUAAUCUCAUGGAGGUAGAGAGUAGAAUGACAAUUACUAGAGGCUGGGCAGGGUGUGUAUGUGGGAUGAAGAGGUGGCUUGAUGGACACAAACAUAGAUAGAAGGAGUGAGUUCUAAUGCUUGAUAGCAGAAUAGGGUGACCAUUGUUAACACUGUAUUGGGUGUUUCAAAAUAGACGGAAUAAAGGAUUUGAAAUGUUCUCAACACAUAGAAAUGAGAAAUACUCAAGGUCAUGGGUAUCCUGGAUACCCUGAGUUGAUCACUACACAUUCUAUGCAUGUAAUGAAAUGUCACAUCUACUUCAAUAAUAUGUACAAAUAUUAUUUAUCAAAAAGCAGGCAUGUAGGUGAGUUGAUUUUCUUCCAUGUCUUCAAACUCCUGGUAAUACUUGUCCACAAAAUUUCUCUAUAAUAACCGGAACAUGUCAUCCAUGAUAAUGUGUACUAUAUAUCCAACCACAACAUCAAAUUCUGUAUCAGAGGCAGAAGAGAAGGACAGCAUGAAGCUCGAUUCCUCCAACUGUCCUUUGGCUGGUGGCCCUCCACCCUGCCCACAGCCCGGCCAGCUCAGCCCCGUCUCUGUCCCAUACAGAGCCACAGCCACAGUGAGAGCCUGGCAGCCUGCCCGGAGGAGGCUUCUUGGCCCAGCCCGGUCAACACCCACAUGCACCACCACCAACUUUUUGCUAUUGUGAAUAACAUAGCUGUAAACAGAUUGCAUAUGAAAGUGCUGUGAAAUCACCAAGGGCUGAGUAGAACAGUUAAGACGAUAGUAGUUGUUUUCUUUCUGGGUUUUUCUCUUGGGCUGGUUUUUGAAAGUGGAUCUACAACAUUGAUAGAGAUCAGUUUUUCUGCUCUUCCAACAUACUGCCAGGACGUGGUCCAGAAAGAUUGGGUACUUUGCAAUACUCAUAGCAAUAUGUGAAGUGAUUGGAAAAAAUGAGACUAUUCAACCAGUUGUUUCAGUGUUGGUUAGGAGGAAAAUGCCCAGAAAGGGGAACAGUUAAUCAUCUACACAAUACCAAGAGCAGGAGGGGAUGACCGACGGCUUCAUCUUUCCUAGUCUAUCCCACACAGACCUUUAGGUGCUCUUUUUUUUCUUUUUUUCGCUCUGUCGCCCAUGCUGGAGUGCAAUGGCGCGAUCUCGGCUCACCACAACUUCCACCUCCCAGGUUCAAGCGAUUCUCCUGCCUUAGCCUCCUGAGUAGCUGGGAUUACAGGCAUGCACCACCACGCCUGGCUAAUUUUUGUAUUUUUAGUAGAGACGGGGUUUCUCCAUGUUGGUCUGGCUGGUCUCGAACUCCCAACCUCAGGUGGUCCACCUGCCUCAGCCUUCCAAAGCGUUGGGAUUACAGGCAUGAGCCAUCGCACCCGCCUCUUUAGGUGUUCUUUUAGGAGCUGGUAGCGGAGGAAGGUGGUUACCCAUCUGUGACAGAGCCUUGGAUGUCACGAGGCCACAGGCUGGCCUUUCCUCCUGUUUACAGGAGGUGAGUUUUCCUGAGUUCCCAGCCUCAGUGUUCUCUGCACAGUCUGUCACUGACUCCCGCUCCCAGUGCUCACUGCCUCUUGUUCUCACUGCCUCCUGUUCUCACUGCCUCCUGUUUCUGCUGAGUUCUUUGCAUCUGCCUGAUGUUGGUUUAAAGCUCCACCCCUCCCAGGGGAAUUUGUCCCAUGAUUCACCUCCUCUUUGGUGAUCUCUUGAUUGCGGCUGCUGCAGCCAUGUAAACCUUAAAGGCGAGCCAAUUUGUUUGUGAUCCAGUGGCCAAAAUGGUUCACCCUCAACUUCCCUUAAUCCCCUGCAGCAUCUGAGACACAUGGGUGAAUGUAUGUAAGGUACUUGGGGCUAACCAAAGUUAAAUACAUAUGACAAGUACCUGAAUCUAGAUAAUCUAAUGGUAAGAUAUCGUUUGCUCUCUGGACUUCAUGGGCUCACCCCAGCAAUGGGGUGCCUGGAAAUGAAGAGAUCUUUCUUGUGUCUCAUCCUCUGGGCUCCCAGCCUCCCUCAACAUCAUGACCUCCAUCUGUAACACCCACCAUCCUGGAGCAGCAUCCUGGAUAUUGGAACUCUGAAGUCUAACCUAAGAGAACAAGGACAAGCCUCUCUAUGAAAGGUUUGCCCUUCCAGAUCCAGUUGAGCUCUGCUCUGGAGCCAGACUCUCUGAAGCAUAGCCCAGCUCUAGCUCUUACCAGUUAUGUGAUCAGGAAUGAGAGUUAAUGUUUCUAUGUUUCUGAUUCUUCAUUUGUAAAAUGAGGAUAAUAAAAAUUUAACUUCA